GUAGCUCCUUCCCCCUGUGGUUUGUGCUGGGCCAGUUGCUGGCUCCCCAAAACCAUUAUCACCAUUAUCAUUAUCACUAUCAUAUCCAUCACCUCACCAUCAUUAUCACUGACAUCAUCACUUUUCUCCAUCACCAUCAUCAUCAUCAUCACUAUCAUCCCCAUCCCCAUCAUCAUCAUUACCAUCAUCAUUGCUGUCGCUAUCAUCAUCAUCAUUCCAUUCAUCACCAUUCAUCAUCACUGUCAUCAUCACCAUCAUCAUCACUGUCAUCACCAUCACCACCACCAUCAUCACCAUCGCCAUCAUCACUGUUAUCGUCACCAUUCAUCAUCACUGUCAUCAUCAUCGUCAUCACUAUCAUCCCCACCAUCACCACCAUCAUUAUCACCAUUCUCCAUCACCAUCAUCACUAUCAUCCUCACCAUCAUCACCAUUCUCCAUCACCAUCAUCAUCAUCACUAUCAUCCCCACCAUCAUCACCAUCACCAUCAUCAUCACUGUCAUCAUCAACAUCCAUCAUCACUGUCAUCACCAUCAUCAUCACUAUCAUUACCAUCACCAUCACCACCAUUAUCACUGUCAUCAUCACCUUUCUCCAUCACCAUCAUCAUCAUCAUCAUAUCAUCAUCAUCAUCAUCAUAUCAUCCUCAUCCCCAUCAUCAUCACCAUCACCACCGUCAUUGCUGUCAUCAUCACCAUUCACCAUCAAUGUCGUCAUCACCAUCAUCAUCACUAUCAUCAUUAUCACCAUCAUCACCAUCACCAUCAUCAUUACUGUCAUCAUCACCAUUCACCGUCACUAUCAUCACUGUCAUUAUCACCAUCAUCAUCACCACCACCAUCACCAUCAUCACUGUCAUCCCCAUCCUCAUCAUCAUCACCAUCACUGUCAUCAUCAUCACCAUCACCACCAUUGCCAUCACCAUCACCAUCAUUAUCACUGUCAUCAUCACCUUUCUCCAUCACCAUCAUCAUCAUCAUCAUCACUAUCAUCCCCAUCCCCAUCAUCAUCACCAUCACCACCAUCAUUGCUGUCAUCACCAUUCACCAUCACUGUCAUCAUCACCAUCAUCGUCAUUAUCAUCAUUGUCACCAUCGUCACCAUCACCGUCAUCAUCACCAUUCAUCAUCACUGUCAUCACUGUCAUUAUCACCAUCAUCAUCACCACCACCACCAUCACCAUCACUAUCAUCGUCAUCAUCAUCACUGUCACCACCAUCACCAUCACUGUCACCAACAUCAUGGUGCUUCUCAACCUUUGGGCUGCUUUGGGUCGUGCUUGACAUGGCACAUUCCUGGUGAGUUAGCUGUUCUUUGGGGGUUUUCUACUGUUGGUGUGGUGAUUAGGGUAGUCAGGACAGGAUGAGUAUAGGCAUAGAGAACCCAAGUGGAUGAUGGUGGAGUGUGAUUCUUCUGAAAGGGUCUUCAUGAGAACCACUGAUCUAGAAGAUUCUGGGAGAAUCUCACGUAUUCUUUCAGGCCCAGGAGUAAGCCAGUGUUACCUGCUCUGUGGAGCUCUCCUUUGUCCCUCCAGGGAGGACAAAUUCUGGCUGGAGCCUGACCUUACUGCUUGUCCAUCUCUCCCAGGGUGGUAGGCCACUUUAGGUAGGACCCUGUGGAUUUCUCCUUGGUGACCCCCGCAUUCUGGGCACAGAGCCUGGAACACAAUGUCUGCCCAGAUGUGUGACUGAACCACCCCCCAAUUCCUUAACUGUAGGAUGGCGGCUGCCUUCAUUAGAAUCUUAACACCUUGCCUGAGGGCUGGCUUUGCAGGUCUGAGUGGCUAGGUCAGGGCACUGCUAGUGUUUUCUAUGUUUGUAGUCAAUUGGUGAGAGUUUGUUUUACGCAUUUGUUAAAACUGUGGGACAGUGGUCUGGAAGCCAACAAGGCUUUAGGGUUGGCAGAGUGACUCCCAUCCCAUCAUUGAUGUCUGGCUUUGACUUGGCAUGGGAGACAUUGCCUCUCCAGAUCUCAGUUCUCUCGUUUGACAAAUGGGGCUUAGGGUUGAACAGCCUCUAAGUCCUCUGUCAGCUCUGCAAUUCAGGAAAGAUGUUUAAAAAUGCAUACUUGCAUUGUAGGUACAUCCAACAUAGAGCAAAGAGAGAAUUUUCCUAGCUAAAUUGACUGCAAAAAAAUGAAACCUCUUGGGCCGGGCGUGGUGGCUCAUGCCUGUAAUCCCAGCACUUUGGGAGGCUGAGGCGGGCAAAUUACGAAGUCAGGAGUUCAAGACCAGCCUGGCCAACAUGGUGAAACCCCGUCUCUACUAAAAGUAUAAAAAUUAGCUGGGCUUGGUGGCGGGCGCCUGUAAUCCCAGCUACUCGGGAGGCUGAGGCAGGAGAAUUGCUUCAACCCAGGAGGCAGAGGUUGCAAUGAGCUGAGAGAUCUGAGCCACUACACUCCAGCCUGGGUGACAGAGCAAGACUCCGUCUCAGGGAAAAAAAAAAAAAAAGAAUCCUCUUAUAAUAUGCAGGCAUCUUAGCAACUGCCAUCUUAGCAACUGCCAUCUUAAGAGGCAGCAUUAUGAUUCAGAAGAAACUGAUAACAUUGAGGAAUACAUUUGUGGAGCACAGAUUAGGAGAGAUUGGUGCAGGGGUGGGGGGUGGCAGGAAGAUAUUAAGGUUGGAAUUUAGGGAGGUGAGCUCUGUGGGUUGGUUUCAUGCAUCCAGCUCACCAUUCAACCUUUCCUGUUAACUUCCUAUAUUAAGGAGGCUGAGAUUAAGAAGACAGGGACUCGUGGCGUAAGGGCGAGACAGACAUAGAGGUGAGUGACUGCAGUGGGAUAUUCACUGUGGGAGCAUUGAAGGUUGGCAGUCAGCUAGAUUCUUAGGCUGUAGAUCGGGGGCCUUAUUUAGAAGCUGUUUACUGUUCCCUUAAGAGGAUCCUCUAGCAGGAAAAACCACUGCUAGGGUUGUUGCUUUCCUCAUUAUAAUGAUGUCUUUAUGUUCGUCUUAGGAGGUGAUAGUACUGAUUAUUUAAGAAACUGGUCAGCCAAACUUCUUAACUAAUUGUGAAUUAGAGAAAAGUCAGAAGUAGGGAGUAUUAUAGAGAUAAGUAAUUGUAUUAUUUUCAGACAAAAGUAUAUGUAGUAAUGUAAACUACUGACCAGAUUUUGUUUCAAAUUGUUUUUUUUAAAUGAAUUGCUAAGAAUUAUUUGAAAUUAGCACAUUAGCGGUAAUAAGAUAGUAGAUAUUAGAUAGAUUAGAUUAGGAUAGUAGGUAGUAGAUGUAGGUAUAAAGAGACUGAAAAUCAGCUGUUUAAACAUUUUUCCCAAAUGUGGGGCUAGGAAGCAAGAUAAAGAAUUAUGCAGGCCAGGCGCGGUGGCUCACGCCUGUAAUCCCAGCACUUUGGGAGGCCGAGGCGGGCGGAUCAUGAAGUCAGGAGAUCGAGACCAUCCUGGCCAACACGGUGAAACCCCGUCUCUACUAAAAAUACAAAAAAAAUUAGCCGGGCGUGGUGGCGGGUGCCUGUAGUCCCAGCUACACGGGAGGCUGAGGCAGGAGAAUAGGGUGAACCCAGGAGGUGGAGCUUGCAGUGAGCCGAGAUCGCGCCACUGCACUCCAGCCUGGGCAACAGAGCGAGACUCCGUCUCAAAAAAAAAAAAAAGAAUUAUGCAGACAGUUUCAUUUCAUUUAUGUUUGGACGGGGAAGAAAGUCAGAAAAUAGAUGGGAAGGAAACAUAUCUAAAUGUUAACGGUGGUUGUAUUCCAUGGGAUCAUGGGUCUUUCUUGAUUUUUCAUGUUUUGCCACAUUCUAAAUUUUCACCAGUGGGCAUUUAUUAUUUUUGCAAUUAGACAGGAAAGAGCCUCCAGGAGGAACUCCAAAUACCCAUCCUUUAUUUACCCUCUUAAUUUGCUUACCAAACUUUCUUGUUAUGGUUAGACUGGCUGGCAUCCAUAAUUUCCAUACUUGUGAUUAUUUAAAUUAAUGGAAAUUUAUCAUAAUCCCUUAUUAAAAUUUCUUCGCUGCACUGAAAUUCAACACUGAGCAAAUCUGUUACCUAGGACAUAAAGAAAAACAUUCAGUCCACGUGCGGUGGCUCAUGCCUGUAAUCCCAGCACUUUGGGAGGCUGAGGCAGGCGGAUCACUUGAGGUCAGGAGGUCGAGACCAGCCUGGCCAACAUGGUGAAACCCCAUCUCUACUAAAAAUACAAAUAUUAGCUGGGCAUGGUGGCUCACGCCUGUAGUGCCAGCUACUCGGGAGGCUGACACAUGAGAAUUUCUUGAACCCAGGAGGUGGAGGUUGCACUGACCCGAGAUCAGGCCACUGCACUCCAGCCUGGGCAACAGAGUGAGACUUGCUCUCAAAAAAAAACAACAUCCAGAGUCUUCCAGGAAAUUUACCGUUUCAGUGUGGCAUAGUGUAGAGUUUGUUUAUUAUCUAGAAUAUGGUUUUUCUUUUUUGUGUUCUUGAACUUGGGCGUUCACUUCGUUUGUUGACCUGGAAGGAGCCAUCUCGGCGCCUGCUGUUUGAACCUUGGGUAUUUUAAUGAAGUGGUUUGAUGUCCUGAUACCACCAGCCCCUGCUGUUGCUUUUCACGGCCCUGGCUUUUCCAGGAAUAAUCUCCUUACUGUUUGUCAUUCUAAUAUGUUUCAGCUCCCUUUUUGAAAAUAACUUUUUCUGCUCCCCUUCCCUGCCCAUUCUUCAUGACCCCCAGAGAAUGGGCCUGCUGGUCUCUAGCCCCUGUGAAUUGGAAGACUCCUGGCGAUGAUCCUUCUUUUUCUCUCUGUGACUCAGGCGGUUGAUGUUGGGUUGACCGUAUUUCUUUGCUGGCUGGUAAGCAGGGCCACCUCAGCCCUUGUGAGGGCCAUGCCUGACUUUCAAUGGCUUCCCUCCAAAGGCUUCUUAGGCCGUUCCUCCCCAUCGUUUUUCAGAGGUUUAAUCUGUUUGAGUCCAGGAUAUUGAGUCAGCAGUGGAAAGUUAUGAAGAUGAGGCCAGCCAUCAGAAAAAUUGGCUAAUAUGAAAGAUUAAUUCCAGGGUGAACAAAGGAGAGGGAUGCUGGGGCCGGGCUGCCUCCCCAGGCAAAUCACAUCACUGUAAAAUCCGAGAAACCAGAAGUUGCCUUUGCUACUCACUCAGUGGCUGCUUGCUGUUUCUUGGAUUAGAUAUUGAAAGAAUCCCAUCUUUAUAGUCUACUGUUCAUAUUUAUGGUCUGGAGAAGAAAAUGUAAUUUUCAGCAAAAUUCUAUCACGUCUGGUAAAUAAUUUCAGGAUCUUUACCUAUGAUACCACAUUAAAAAAAAUUCGUAUGGCUUCAGCAUUCAGAAAUUGUUCUUUUCAAACUCUGGGCCCUCGGGUUAUUACAAGAUUUAACACCGAGGCAGGAAGCCUGCUCGCCUAUCACUGGAGACAGGUAGGUUGCUAUGGAGACCAGGUGUGUGUCCCUGCGGUUUCCUGGGUAUCCCAGUUGUCCUGGAAAAGAAAUCAGCUCACUUUAUGUGAUAUUUCUGCAAUAGUGUGUGUGAAUUAAGUUUUUCUAAACACAGAUCAGAUGUUUUUGUUGACUUACAGUGUGAUUUCUGACAUAAUUUUGUCCUCGGUUUUGUUUUGCUUAAUUAUGAAUCCUACAUAACCCUACCUUUUCCUAUCAGAAGCACUUCCAUGCAUCAAGACCCCCUAUCCAAAACAGCCACAACAACUUCACCAACAAAAUCUCUUAAAGCUAGAGAUGCCUGCUUUGGUGUGAAUGAUGAUUACCCCUUAAAAUAAUUCAACAAUUUUUUUUUUUUUUUUUUGAGACAGGGUCUCAGUCUGCCUCUCAGGCUGGAGUGCAGUGGCGUGAUCUCGGUUCACUGCAUCCUGUGCCUCCUGGGUUCGAGCAAUUCUCCUGCCUCAACCUCCUGAGUAUCUGGGAGUACCGGGAUGCACCACCAUGCCUGGCUAAUUUUUGUAUUUUUAGCAGAGACGGGGUUUCACCAGGUUGGCUAGGCUAGUCUCAAACUCCUGACCUCAGGUGAUCCACCCACCUUGGCUUCCCAAAGUGCUGGGAUUACAGGUGUAAACCACCAUGCUCGGCCUCAACAAUUAUUAUAUAUGGUUUGCCAGAUCCUGGCCUGGGCACUGGGGAUGCAAGAUAGAGCAAGACCAUUGGAGGCCCUGCCCUGGCGGAGCUUGUAUUAGGGUUGUGAUCCUAGACCACAUGAAGCCCACAAGGGGGCCCUGGGCUCACCCGUUCCUGGCUCACAUUCACUGUCAGCCACAGCUAAACCUCGGGGCCUGGAACCUCUCUUGUUGUCCCCAUGGGACGAGUGGGCACAUGCCUUGUUGGAUGGACAAUAACAUCAUCUGUUUUUGUUUGAUGUGUUAUUAUUCAGAGGCAUUUUUCAGAAUGGAGAACAGUGCCUUAUCAGUCUGCUUCUGAUAAUUUUAUACAUGAAAAAAAUCCUAUUUGUGCAUAUUCUUGGGUCUCUCCCCAUUUCUAAAGGCAGUCAACUUGGUGGUUGGCUGUAAAAAGCUCUUUACACUUCCUAGGACUUGUCAAAUAUUGACAAGUCUUUCUCCUUUCAUCCAGUUCAGCACCAGCAUCCUCAAACUCACUGAAACAGAGCAUCCCACAGUGGCAGCCACUGUAGGCCCCAGGUGGGUAUCCUACUCCUCCACCCCCGCCCCAGACUCCCCCAACCCCAGCUCGCACCUGCAGAAGUUACGUCUUUGCAGUUAUUUCAGGAGAAAAAGGCGGCCACUCUUUCUCUCCCUUCUUUGGGUUUGUGUUCAGCAAGGGUCUACUGCAGUCCCGGUGCCGGACAGCCUGUUUUGCCCAUGCUUGUUAACUGAUGGGGUCCUCAAGUGGCCUUGUGACAGGCCUGAUAAGGCCGCACGUGGGUGUGGUUAGAGUUGAUGACCGCUCCGGACAUUGGCGAUGUGAGGAAAGUGACAGACUCCAGCCUCCAUGUGCAGCCGGUGAUUGGCCGGGUGGGCUCGGUUUUCUAGUGGCAAAGGAUGCUGUGAUCUGAAUAAGAAAACAAACCUCAGGCCCCAAGUGCCACGGGCUUAGAGACUUGAGAGGAGGUGCUUGCAACUCCAUCUGGGAGGCUAAGGGCAGCCAAGAGCUGCUGUCUUGAGGCUGACCCACUCCCUUGCAGUGUAAUGGGUAGUGAACAGGCCAUCCUUUUUAAAGGAAAAUAAGUGCCUCCCUAUGGACUCUGUUCCUAUCCUGCUACCCUCCCUGAAGCUUGAAUAGCACCCACCCGUGCCUUCUCCAUGCCAGCCCUUGGGUCUGCCGGGACCACUGCCAUGCUUUUGAUGGACACGGCCUUGUAGCGUCUAUAUCCUCAUCUGUGAAAUGGGAAUUCCACAGCCUCCCUUUCGCAGGCUGCUUGUAAUAGUUGCCAUUAAACCUCUUCUGAACUCUAAAGUGCUGUAUCAAUGUAAGGACCAUCAUCAACAUCAUUGUCGUCCUCAUCGUGAGUCUUUCCAAAUUCACCUCCUGCUGCCCCAGCACGGGAGUGUCUGAGACUGCAGGUUUCCUUGAUGGGUUCCUGGGGCUUCCCUUGUGGAAAUUUGAGUUCUGAGCCUUCUGCACUUUUCCAUCCCCCAGUCUGGAGUCAACCUGUAUUUUUCAUUUUCCCUCUGCAAGAUGUCAGCCCAUAGGAGAGGCCUGGAGGCUUGCAGGGGAAAUGGGACGAUGUUUGAAGGAAGCCCCCGUGCCUGUGGGAGCAUGCAGCCUCCUCCGUCUUUUUGUCUGCCAGGCAGGGGAGUAAUUUGCCGUUAUGUACUGGGCAGUCUGGGAGCUGGACUCUCAGAUGAAAAAUGCUUGUUCAAGCACAGACAGCCAGGCAUGGCUCAAAUCAGAGCAUCGAUUUAGCAAGCAGCUCUGCUCAAACAGCCAGCUGUGUGAUCACCUUUUCAGGGGAUGAUAGGCUGACGGGCAGGUGGGGUGGGGUGGGGUGGGGUGGGGUGGGCAGACUAAUACAGGGACCCUGUGUUUGGGAGCCUCUGUUUAAGCAGAGACCGGGCCUGGAGAGAGUAUCCCUGGGUAGGGAAAGGUGCUCUCACAUUAGUGGGUUCCACCUGGCCCCUUGGUGGAGCUCCCAUUCAUUCAUUCACUCAUUCACUCAUUCAUUCACAUCGUGUCUACUAUGUGCCAGUCUCUGUGCUAAGAGAGUGAUCCAAGCAGAAGGUCUGAAAUCCUCAGGGAUUCGUUUCCCAGCCGACUUAUGCCUUACUAAGUGGAGCAGGUUCUGGGCUGCAGGGGACUGACUUGCUGCUGCAGGUCUGGGUCUUGAACUAAGGGAGAAAGACAAUGCCCAUCUUCUUCUUGGCGCAGUCAUUUGAGGAGAGGAGCAUUUGCUUCUUGCCAACCUGCCUGCCUGGGAGGCCCUCUUGCUCCUGCAGCCCCCCGAGUCCCCUUUGCAGCUCCCAGUCUUGCUUGGGGUUGCCUCCUCCAAGAAGCCUCCUGGGCUAGCUCAGGCAUCCUGUGGAGGCACUGCUGGGCCACUGAUGCCUGAGCUCCUGUGGCCUGGCUGUCUGCAGGGCUUCAGUCCUGGCCUUUCACUUCCCAGACAUGAGUCUUAUCUUUCCACUUGGUUAGGGCCUCCCCACGGACAUGGACGGAUAUGGUUUGGAUUUGUGUCCCCACCCAAAUCUCGUGUUGAAUUGUAAUCUCCAGUGUUGGAGGAGGAGCCUGGUGGGGGGUGAUUGGAUCAUGGGAGCAGAGUUCCUCUUGCUGUUCUCAUGAUAGUGAGUGAGUUCUCACGAGAUCUGGUUGUUUGAAAGUGUGAAGCACCUCCCCCUGCUCUCCCUUCUGCUCCAGCCAUGUAGGACGUGCCUGCUGUCCCUUCUGACGUGAUUGUAGGUUUCCCGAGGCCUCCCCAGCCAUGCUUCCUGUGCAGUAUGUGGAACCGUGAGCCAAUUAAACCUCUUUUCUUUAUAAAUUACCCAGUCUCAGGUAGUUCUUUAUAGCAGUGCGAGAACUGACAGGGACCGUGUGUUUGGGAGCCUCUGUUUAAGCAGAGACCGGGCCUGGAGAGAGAAUCCCUGGGGAGGGAAAGCUGCUCUCACAUCAGUGGGCUCCACCUGGCACCUUGGUGGGGCUCCCAUUCAUUCAUUCAUUCACUCACUCAUUCAUUCACAUAGUACCUAGUAUAUGUGCCAGUCUCUGUGCUAAGAGAAUGAUCUAGGCAGAAGACCUGCCCGCUCAGGGCUUCUGUUUCUAGCUGGGAGCAACAACAGUAAACUAAAUAAGCAGAUUAUAUUGUAUAAUAUAGUAAUACUUAGAAGGUGAUGAGACUGUGGAAAACAAUACAUUAGUGAAGAGGGUGAGGGUAUUGGAUGGAAGAGCGUGAGUGUAUUAGGCCGUUCCACAUUGUUAUAAAGAAAUACCUGAGACACGGUCAUUAAUAAAGAAAAGAGAUUUAAUUGUCUCACGGUUCUUCAGGCUGUACAGGAAGCAUGGUGCUGGCAUCUGCUCAACUUCUAAGGUGGCCUUGAGAAGCUACAAUCAUGGCGGAAGGUGACGGGGGAGCAGGCACGUCACAUGGAGAAAGCAGAAGCAAGAGAGAGAAAAAUGCAAGGUGCCACACACUUUUAAACAACCAGAUCUUGUGAGAACUCACUAUCUCGAGGACAGAACCAAGGGGAUGGUGAGAAACCAUUCAUGAGAAAUCCACCCACAUGAUCCAGUCGUCUCCCACCAGGCCUCAUCCCCAACUCUGGGGAUUACAAUUCAACAUGAGAUUUGGUUGAGACAUCCAAGCCGUAUCAGUGAGAGAUGCAGUUUUUUUUUUUCAGGGGAAAGUGUUGUUGUUGUUGUUGUUUUAAUAAGAUAUAAUUUACAUACCAUAUACCAUGAAAGUCGCCAUUUAAAAAUGUACAAUUCAGUUGCUUUUAGUAUACUGGCAAAGUUGAGCACCAGUAGCUACUAAUUUCAGAACAUUUUCAUCACCCCAGAAAAAAAUCUCAUAGCCAUUAGCAGUCACUCCUCAAUCUCCUCGUGCCCUAGGCCCUGGAAACCAAUAAUUUACUUUAGGUGUCUCUGGAUUUGCCACUUCUGGACAUUUUAUAUCAAGGAAAUCAUGCAAUAUGAGGCCUUUUGCAUCUGGCUUCCUUUACCAAGCACAGUGUUUUCAUGCACCGCCAAUGCUGCGUGUGUAUCUGUACUGCAUGCCUGUAGAUGGCGGAAUAAUAUUCCAAUGUAUGGAUAGACCACAUUUUGUUUAUCCAUUCAUCUGUUGAUGAACAUUUGGGCUGUUUUCACUUUUGGCUAUUCUGAACAAUGCUGCGAGGAACAAGUUUUUUUUGUACAAGCGUGCAAGUUUUUUGUGGAUGUAUGUUUUCAUUUCUCUUAGGCAAAUAGAGAGACACAAUUUUACUUUUUAUUUAUUUUAUUUUUUAUUUUUUUAGAGACAAGGUCUUGCUCUGUUGCCCAGGCUGAAGUGCAGUGGCGCCAUCAUAGCUCACUGUAGCCUGCAACUCUAUGGAUUACAUGUUCCUCCUGCCUCAGCCUCUUGAGUUGCUGGGACUACAGGCAUACCCCAUCAUUCCUGGAUAAUUUUUAAAUGUUUAGUAGAGAUGAGUUCUCACUAGAUUGCCCAAAUUCGUCUUGAACUCCUGGGCUUAAGUGAUCCUCCCAAGUUAGCCUUAUAAAGUGCUGGGAUUAGAGGCAUGAACCACUGCACCCAGCCACAGUUUUAAAUAGGGUGGUCAGAGAAGGUCUCAUGAGAAGGUGACAUCUGAGCAAAGACUUGAAGAAAAUAAGGGCAGAAGCCACACGAAAACCCCAGCAGGACAGCAGGUGCAAGGGAACAGCAAGUGCAAGGAUGCUUCCACCAAGGGGCUGGAAAAUGAAAGGCUUGACUUCACCAGCUGCCUCCCAACCAGGGGGCCCAGUGAGUUUAGGCCUCACUGGCCCUUUCUGGCUGAGGGGCAGCCUGCUGCGAGGGGUUUCCCUUUCUGAAUAAAGAGUCAAAGUCCCAAGACAGAUGAUUUUUGACCCAUGCAUCUUCUUCCUGCCUGGAAAGCAGAUGUGAUUCCUGGAGAUGGGGCAGCUGUUCUGUGGCCAUGAGGUUGAAAUCCAUGUGCUAAAGACAGUAGAGCAGAAGAAGACUGGGACCUUGAUGGCAUUCUUGAGCUACCGCCUGAACCUUGGAUCUCCUGCACCUGAACUUUGCUCUGUGACACAAAGAAGACCCUUUCUUAUCUAAGCCACUCUUAUCUAAGCCACCGCUUGUCACGUUUUAUGUUGUUUGCAGCCAAAUGCAUUCCUCAUUGAUGGAAUGUCCAACAUUGUCCCCAAGUCCCCCAGAUAGAUCCCUGGGGGCUCUUGACAGACAGACAGCAGGCAAGCCUGGGACACACGCUGCCCCCUUCUGCUUUCCUGUCCCUCCAUCGUGUUAAGCUGGUCUCUCAGGUGGGCAUCAGGAUUCAGCUAUCCCAGGCUGACCCUGAGGUCCACCAUGACUGUGCUGCAGCCACCACCACUGGCCGCUUCAUGGCAUGUUUCCAGCACAACUCUCUGACCUGGCUCCCCCGGUUCCCCAGACGCGUUCCCCACGGAGUCCCAGCGUGUAUGCAUGGGGUCACGGUGCUCCACGCUCUCAACCGUUGGUUGCAGGUUCCCGUCCAGCCUCUCAAGCUGGCUGCUCCCCUUUCUCAGUUGUCCCCUGUGCCUCUUGUACCCUAACUUCAGUGUUAGAGCACCUUUCAGGGGGAAUGGCGUAAAAAAGCCUUCCUUUCCAGUAGACAGAGUGCCCUGGCCAGCAGAGGCCAAACACAUUCCCAUUCAGCUUUGUUUCAUGCUGGAUCUGGCCCCAGGCCUGCACCUGGCCCUGGCAGUGGGCGCACGUUAGGUGGGAUUGCUGAAGACAAUGGGUGACUGAGGCAGUUACAGGUGUCAGCCCCAGAUGAGGCUCCCCAACCUGUACCCUUUACCCUGGAGCUGGCCCCAUCUCUCACAGCCCAGUGGUGUACUACCUUAGGUAAGCACCAGUUGCGCCUCACUCUAAUGAAAAUAAUAAAAGCUCAAAUGACCAGCACUGUCCUACUGCUUUAUACGCAUGACCUCAGGUAAUGAGAAUUAGCCCACAUCCAUUCAUUCCACAAAUAUUUAUGGAGUGCCUACUGUAUGCCAGGGAUUCUUCCAGGCACUGGGGAGACAUUUAAAAAACAAUAACAACAACAACAAAAAUCUGCGUCUUGUCGGAACUUCCAUAUACACUUCCACUGGCUACUUCAUGGAAACAUCUGGAACAUCUGAUUUUUCUAGUCUUCCCAUUACUAAAUGUGGCACAAGAACGUAGUCUAAAGGAUGUACUUCACCAUGCAAAAGCUCUUGUCAUUUCAGAAAAGGAAGGAGAAUUAAGUAAAAUGUACUUCAAGAAAGUCAGUUAAGAAUUUUUCCAGUUAAUGAAAAUUUAAAAUGAUUGGCUUUCAUCUUGCUGUUUUCCAGGGUCCCACUAUUAAGAACUCACUCAUCCUGUUGUUAUUAAGGGUGAAACCCAGACAUUUCCUUAUGUAAAAGCCAAUUAAAAUAAAUUAAAUGCAAAUACUGUUUCAUUGUCAUGUCAGUUUUGAGAACCGGAUCAAUCAGAGGUUGUGGAAAUGCCAAAGUUGUUAAGGCUGUGGUUACCAUGACAACAGCUCUAUUGUGUAAGUGGUCUGUUAUUUGGGAAUUCUUCCUUAGGUCAGGCUAACAGUGAUGUCAUUUCUCAGGGAAGGGGACGGAGUUCUCUGGAGUCAGGUCUGGGGCCAGGAGACCUGGUGAGCAAAAACUGGGGUUCAGCCAGAACUACCAGUUUUGUGACCAUGGGAGACAGUCCCUUCCCCUUUUGCCUCAGUUUCCUCGCUUUGGGGAUAGCCAUUGCACAGCUAAUUCUAAGGCAAGGAUGAAAGUCUUCUCUAUUCUUGAGGUGCUGGGGUUCCUCAGCCUCCACCGUCCAGCCUCGAGCAGCUGCCCCCUCUCACCUGCUCCUCAGCCUUCUGGAACAGACAGGCCCCCCACAGCAGCCCAGCCCAGGCCACCAGCACCACCCCCAGAGGUUUAUGCCAUCUUCAUGCAGUGGGAGGCUCAGCCCCCACACUGGGACCUGUCCACUUUAGCCCCAAGGAUCUUACCAAGGUCAAAUCUUUGGAACUCAGGGUCUUUGGGAACUUCUGGGCCAGACAACCCGGCCAUCACAGGGGCUUCUGCGGGGUUGGCUUUAUGAUGCAUUUGGGUCAGGAGGUCUGUUUUUAUCCUUUGGGCCUCUGGGAAAGUCCGUCCUGGCCAAGUCCUCUGUCCCCUAGUCUCAUGGCUGGCUGGCCCUGGAGCUCGGGUGGCCUGGCCCGGCCCGCCUGCUUCCCCACAGGCAGCGGCUCUUGCUUCUGCUGCCUGCAGUGCUCCAGAUGCUGCAGGCUCCUUCCUUCCUUCAGGGCAUCCUAAGUCCCCCGAGUCUCGAAUCCCCAGUCUCAGCUGAGUCCUCGAGGUCAGUGGGGCAGAACGCCAGAGCCCUGGGACAACGGGCUGCAUAAAACACUUAUUUUAAUUAUAAGAGUGAUGUAAGAACAUAUCAGAAAAUUGGCAAAAUACAGGGCAAAAAAAAAAAAUCACUGGUGGUCGCCUUCUCACACAGUCACACACAGUGGUGUGCAGCCUUCUGGCUUUUGGUUGCUUUGUUGCAGUAUUGGCACCUGCGUUACAAGAUUUUGUGUUGACCAUUCUUGUUCUUGCUGUGGUCUUUAAGGUUUACAGCGACAGCUGUUCCUCUUCAGGAUGCAAGGAGACCGAGCCUGCCUGCCCUCAGGGAGCUGACGGUCCAGCAGGAGGCAUCCUGUCUGCAGGGCCCAUGCGGGGGACAGGGCAAGAGGGGCAUGGUCUAGUGGCCCAGUCAGGACGCGGAAACACUCCCUGGAGGUUCUGACCCACUCCCUCUCAGCCUCCGCCUGGUCUCUGGGUUGGCUGUUCCAGCUCCAAAGAGAAGGAGGAACCUUUUCCUUCUGCAGCCCCUCCCCACCAGCCUCAUUCCUUAGCUGGGGUCAGACCUGGGGUCCUCACUGCAGCUGGCCUCUGGCAGCGUUCUCAGGCUAGCCCUCCCUGCUGAAAAGAGAACCGUGUGGGACUCACAGGUGUAGUCGCCGCCGCCAGCCGCCAUGGGCAAACAGAACAGCAAGCUGCGGCCCGAGGUGCUGCAGGACCUGCGGGAGAACACGGAGUUCACCGACCACGAGCUGCAGGAGUGGUACAAGGGCUUCCUCAAGGACUGCCCCACCGGCCACCUGACCGUGGACGAGUUCAAGAAGAUCUACGCCAACUUCUUCCCCUACGGCGACGCUUCCAAGUUCGCCGAGCACGUCUUCCGCACCUUCGACACCAACGGCGACGGCACCAUCGACUUCCGGGAGUUCAUCAUUGCGCUGAGCGUGACCUCGCGGGGCAAGCUGGAGCAGAAGCUCAAGUGGGCCUUCAGCAUGUACGACCUGGACGGCAACGGCUACAUCAGCCGCAGCGAGAUGCUGGAGAUCGUGCAGGCCAUCUACAAGAUGGUGUCGUCUGUGAUGAAGAUGCCGGAGGAUGAGUCCACCCCGGAGAAGCGCACAGACAAGAUCUUCAGGCAGAUGGACACCAACAAUGACGGCAAACUGUCCUUGGAAGAAUUCAUCAGAGGUGCCAAGAGCGACCCCUCCAUCGUCCGCCUGCUGCAGUGCGACCCCAGCAGUGCCAGUCAGUUCUGAGCGAGCGGCCCCUGGACAGUUGCAGAGAAACACAGGCUUGUCGUGCCGUUUAAGCUUUGCUUGCAAGAGUGGAUGCCCCGCAAUCGUUCCUGCUCUCCCGGGCCCCGGGCCUGGGGCAUGCGUUGCACCUGCCCAGCCCGGUGGCUGCGCCUCCCUCCUCCACCUGACCAACGCGACAUUCCUCCCCUCACGCCUGGCCCGGUCCCUUCCAGGGCAACUCCCAGGGAUGUGGUGACAUGCAGGGUUCAAGUGUUCUUGGUUCCAGGCACCUCCCGGCUCACGGGGAGCUCAGAGGUCCAUGCCGAGGAGACCAGGCAGGACCUCCCGAGGCUGCGCCCCGGCCGGCCCAUGCGUUUUGUGAUCCCAAGUGACUCUGUGGGAAGGGUGGGGACGAGGCGUCGGGAGGGUAUACAGGGAGCCCCUCCCGUGCAUGGCUGCCCCCCCGUUCAUUUUCUCCACCACAGCCGCUUGCACGUAUAGAUACUGUGGUCCCCUUUCUUUUAAUAUAUAAAUUAUGUAUGGUGAAGUGGAGUGUAUUGUGUAGGUCCCGUAUUUAAUGCCUCUGACUGCCUUUGAAGCGCAGCCCUCUGUGGCCCGCAGCCCCCUGAGCCUGGCUGUUGUGUGGUAUUUAUGCUCUCUUUGUCUGCCUGUUUCUAAGGAAAUGCAUGUGUGCCCUGAGCCGUGAUGAUCCUCCCAUCCGUGUUGUGAGCACAGGCAUUUGUGUCUGGUCUGUCCUCCCUGUUGAUUGGUCUGGCAUUUCCGGUAUUAAAAUGAUAAAAUAAA